AGAGUGUGGUCAGGCGGCUCGGACUGAGCAGGACUUUCCUUAUCCCAGUUGAUUGUGCAGAAUACACUGCCUGUCGCUUGUCUUCUAUUCACCAUGGCUUCUUCUGAUAUCCAGGUGAAAGAACUGGAGAAGCGUGCCUCAGGCCAGGCUUUUGAGCUGAUUCUCAGCCCUCGGUCAAAAGAAUCUGUUCCAGAAUUCCCCCUUUCCCCUCCAAAGAAGAAGGAUCUUUCCCUGGAGGAAAUUCAGAAGAAAUUAGAAGCUGCAGAAGAAAGACGCAAGUCCCAUGAAGCUGAGGUCUUGAAGCAGCUGGCUGAGAAACGAGAGCACGAGAAAGAAGUGCUUCAGAAGGCAAUAGAAGAGAACAACAACUUCAGUAAAAUGGCAGAAGAGAAACUGACCCACAAAAUGGAAGCUAAUAAAGAGAACCGAGAGGCACAAAUGGCUGCCAAACUGGAACGUUUGCGAGAGAAGAUGUACUUCUGGACUCACGGGCCUGGGGCCCACCCAGCACAGAUCUCUGCUGAGCAAUCUUGUCUCCACUCUGUUCCUGCCCUUUGCCCAGCCCUGGGCCUCCAAUCUGCAUUGAUUACCUGGUCUGAUCUCUCUCACCAUCACUAGGUACUUAAUAAAUAUUUGCUGUUGAUGAUAGCAAUGACCUUGAGACUGAUGAACAGUCUGGCCAAGAGGAUCCUUGAUGUGGAAGAUAGAAAAAGCCUUUGGGGUCAGGCAGACUUGGAUUCUAAUACCAGCCAGUUCUGCUUGCUGUGUCUGAGCCUCAGUUUACUCAUCUGUGAAGAGGAGGUAGCAAGAAUGAAAAUGCCUGCCUUGUGGUUUGUUGUAAGGACAGACACUGCCAACGUAGAGGGCCCAGCAGCUCACAGACCAGUUGCUCUGAGAGCAGACCACUCUUGCCUUGAUGGUAGGGAACUAUUUUUGUGCGUGGCAAGUGGGACCUUAGGAAGGAAGGCAACUGUGAGGCUUCUGAGAAGGACCCUACACAAGGGAGUUUCCUCCCAGGGCAGGUGAAUGGAGAGGGUGGCAGAAGCCUACGGGAAGGGGUCACAGGGAUCAGCUAGAGAGUGCCACCACCCUUCCUGGGGAAUGCAGGGCAAGGUCCCUGGUGGGAGUUUUCCUGGGAAGCCAAAGAAGCGCCCAACAAAGACAGAAUCAACAUUUGGGUACCUUUGGUACCCAGAGGCAGCAAUGCCAACUACAACCACACUGGAAGAAGAAGACCUUCUCCGCAUAGAUUCUCUGAUCUCUUCCUCCUUCAUGGCACCAGCCCUGGGGAACCAGCAUGGUGGGGAAAUAAUGAAGCUGGAAUACAACCACUUACAGACUUCACAACCUCCUCCUGUAGAUACCAAAGGGAUUUUAGGAUCACAUUUUAUUUCUCACCUGAGCAAGAAAAGCUACAGGAGCAUCUCAAGCAGAGGGCAGGAGUCUCCAGAGGAGUUCAAGGGGCUCUGGCAAGAAAAAUCAAGGGGCUGUGUUCAAGAACUGGCUCCCUUGGUGAUUGUAUUACGAAGCCCAUGUGUGCUGGAUGCUGAUGAAAUUGCUGCCAAAUGCCUGUGCAGCCUUGGCAAGGCCCUUUAUUUCUCUGGGUCUCCAUUUCUCUCUCUCUUUUUUUUUUUUUUUUUUUUUUGAGGCAGAGUCUCACUCUGUCGCCCAGGCUGGAGGGCAGUGGCGUGAUCUCGGCUCACUGCAAGCCCCACCUUCUGAGUUCACGCCAUUCUACUGCCUCAGCCUCCCGAGUAGCUGGGACUACAGGCGCCCACCACCACGCCCGGCUUAUUUUUUGUAUUUUUAGUAGAGACGGGGUUUCACCGCAUUAGCCAAGAUGGUCUCGAUCUCCUGACCUCGUGAUUCACCCACCUCAGCCUCCCAAAGUGCUGGGAUUACAGGCAUGAGCCACUGCGCCCGGCCUGGGUCUCCGUUUCUCUAGCUGUGAAAUGACUGUUCUAAAAGAGCCCUGCCGGACUUUGGCAGUCUGUAAGAAGACCUGAGUUCUUCUCUCAGUUCCAAGCAGGAAAAUUGAACAUACCCUGAGCCCAGAGCCUGCAACAAACUCUGGGCAGCCUCAGGAAGUCAGGCAGUGAAGUCGGAAAAAUGAUCUCUUCUGUAUAGGGAGAAAAUAAAAGUUUAAAAAUUUGUAGUUUGAA